AGGCCGCCCUUUCCCUGCGGGUGGGAACUCCAGAUGGACGAGGGCCCACCCCACCCGGCGCUUCCCCGUGCAGCCCGGGGUCGCGGCGGGCGGCGAGGGCAGCGGCUCCCCGGCUCCCCUACCUUACCUUCCCUGUCCUUCUCGUCCGCCAUCUUGCUGCGGAGCCGGUCGCCUGGGAGAUGCCUAACGAUAACCUCGGCCGCGGUGUCCCGGCCUGCUCAGCGCCCCGCGGCGAGCCUGGCCUGAGGAGGGGCCGCUCUGAAUCCCGGGGGAGGAAGACCCUUGGGCGGGGCGGGGCGGGGAGGAGGCUCCGAGCGCGCCCUGUCCCCGUUUCGCGCCACGACCCUCGCGCUGGGGGAAGACCAGAGGCCCCGUCUGCCACCCGGCCCCCGGCCUUGUCCCUCCAGACCCGAGGCCGGAGCCGGACUUGUCCCGGGCCUAGCAUGUUGCUUCAUCACACGGUCCCCAACCCCUCCUUUCCCUUAUUUCUCAUCCAUUUGGGGACAGCACGCGCGCGCACACACCCCUCGCCCCCUCCUGUCCUGUUUGUGCGACGUGGCGUUGCUCGAUUUUUGUUGUUAACUGCAGAUUUUGAAAAGCGCCGGAGAGCUAGGUGAAGAGCUGGGCUCCCAAGGGGGUGAUAGAACCAGCCCGCGGCCCGGCCUCCUCCUCCCGCUUCCCAUUCGCAGCCCGCCUCCCGCCGGGAAGCGGCCCGGCUGCUGCAGAACGGCCGCGCCUGCCCUCCCGGUUUCUCCCGUCCAGUCUUCACCGUCCUUUCCCAGAGAAAGCGACAGCACAGCCUAUGACAACCGAAGCUAAAACGGAAAAACUGGGCCGGGCGCAAGAGGAAACCAGAGCCAUUCGACUAUUGCUAGAGGAGAGGAAUAGCUGCAGGAAAACAUGCGCAAAAUAGCACAAACAUUGCGUCGUCAAGGCUGCAAUGUCUAAUACAAAAUAGAAGGUUCUCAUAGCAACAAAAACGUGCCCAUGUUGUGCUCAGUAUUACAUGCGUUAAAAUGUUCUUAGUUGUGAAAUUUGACAUGACCGCUAGUUAAAGUUACAAUGGAAGUUUUAAAUCCCGCUUUCCGAAAACUUUGCAGCUAUAGCAUGAAGUUAAAUUUUUGUCUUAUUUUCUGGAUAAGUUUACUAUACUGGAACAUAGUAAAGCUCUUUUUAUAAAGAGCUUUGAAUAAAAUACCUAAUGAUGUGGUUGAAACGAACACCUAUUUUCAAAACUAAUCUUAAGUGGUAUUUCAGUGCAUAUGUUAUGUAAAAGCAAUUUAUAAACUAAAUUUUAAGAGCCUUCAAAAUACAAGGUACUCGUAUUUAAUGACUUAACAGUUUUAAUGCUUUUAUUGUUUCUAUAAUCUCUCAGGAAAUCCUAAAACUGACUAUAUUUUUCUUUAUUAAAAUAACUUUUUCUGUAGAAGAUACCCAUUUGGCGCUGUGAUCAGCAUUCUACUUGAAAUUGAAUAUAAACAACUGAAUCAUUACAAAAUGGCUCAUGUUAGAAGAUACUUAAAACGAAUACAAUCUUGUACAGUAAAUGUUUAACACCCCAAAAUAACGAAAAGUAAUUAUUAGCAUUCAUUUAUAUCUAAAUCUCAGUCAAUAUGAUCUAAAUAUUUGUGUUUAAAGACUCCCCCUUUCCAUAUAGAUAAUGAAGGGCUUUGAAAUAAGUGUAGGAAACCCUAAGUUUGGUCUCAGGCUUCCUAUUCAUUCACUAUGCUUUUUCGUGUGCUGUUUACAGUUUCCUUUUUCUGGAAUGCCUUUCCCUGCUUUUUUCCCCCGCCAACAUUUCAGCUUCCCACAGACACACAUUUGUGCCCUCCUGGUUGUCCUGCAGGAUGACCUUUGUUUUUGUUUUUGUCUUUUGUUUUUCGAGACAGGGUCUCGCUCUGUCGUCCAGGAUGGAGUGCAGUGGUGUGAUCUCUGCUCACUGCAACUUCCGCCUCCCGGUCUCAAGUGACCCUCCCACCGCAACCUCCCAAGUAGCUGGGAGGAGCGGCGCGCGCCACCAUGUCUGGCUAGUUUUUGUAUUUUUUGUAGAGACAGAGUUUCCCCAUGUUGCCCAGGCUGCUCUCAAACUCCUGAGCUCAAGCGAUCUGCCGCCUGCCUGGCCCUCCCAAAGUUCUGGGAUUACAGGUGUGAGCCACUGUGCCUGGCCAGGAUGACCUUUUUGAAGUCACCUAGUCAUUGAAGCUUUCCCUCUCAGCCUUUUCCUCUGUGGCCCCAUGCUUAUAGAGCCUCCCACAUUGAUUUGCAGUGCCUUCGUUCGUUCACUUUAUUUCCACCUACCAAACAGUAAGAUCUUGAAGACAGAAACGGCAUUAUUCGUUUAUAUAUCCCCGGUAUCUAGUACAAUUUUUCUGUUUGCAAUAAUAAAUGUCUUAAAACUUAAGAAAGGAGUAAGUCUUCUCAAUGACUUUUUUUAAAAAAGACCCAGAUUCAGCACUUAUUGUAUGUAAGACAGACCUUCCUUUUACAUUACAUUUUUCAUCAGUAAAAGUACUGGGCCAGGCGCGGUGGCUCACGCAUAAUCUCAGCACUUUGGGAGGCUGAAGCGGGUGGAUCACUUCAGGUCAUGAGUUAAAGACCCACCUGGCCAACAUGGUAAAACCCCAUCUCUACUAAAAAUAGAAAAAUUAGCCGAAUGUGGUGGCUCACGCCUGUAAUCCCAGCUACUCGGGAGGCUGAGACAGAAGAAUCGCUUGAACCCAGGAGGCAGAGGUUGCAGUGAGCCGAGAUCCGCCACUGCACUCCAGCCCAGAUGACAGAGCAAGACUCCAUCCCCAAAAAAAGGUACUAGUAUUUCAUGUUAAUAAAAUGGAAUUCUUAUAUAAACAUAUAUAAAUUAAAAAUUAUUUUAAGAGUUGAACAGAUUUCUCUGCAAAUCCCCCUAUAUUUUUAUAUUUUUUAAACUAACUGUAUUCAGCAAAGCUUUUUAUUAUUUAAUUUAUUCCAAACCACAUUAAUCAGUAUUUCUCUGAACUCCUACAGCACAUUUAAAACAGUACUGUUUCUCUAGGUGUGGGUGAGUAAAAAAAUAUUUAAUAUAUGUUAAUUAACUUCCGCAUCUCCUGACCCCACUAAGGUUUGAAUAGGAGCCUCCCCCUUUAUAAACCCUUUUUAUAUACCCACACUACCUAGCCUAAUUGGGGCACAUAUUAGCUGCUUCAUACAUACUUUUCAACUGCCUAAUUUGCUGAUUAGGCAUAAAAGUAUAUAAUUCUGGAAAAGUCUCCACAAGGUGAAAAUGAUUAUCCAAAUAAUAAAGGCCCACAAUGCCAGUGAGUACAUUAUCUGCAUUAUGCUGAUAUUUGACUCCUUUCAACUCUCUUUGGUUGUAGAAACAUGACCGAUGAUUAUAUUACACUUUUAACUCUUUAAAUAUUAUUAGCUUGCUUUGGACUGUGGAAAACUAACUACAAUCAUUUUUAUUCCUCAGAAUAUAUUUUGCGGCCGGGCACGGUGGCUCAUGCCUGUAUACCCAGCACUUUGGGAGGCCGAGGUGGGCAGAUCACGAGGCCAGGAGUUCGAGACCAACCUGGCCAAUAUGGUGUAACCCCGUCUCUACUAAAAGUACAAACAUUAGAGUUUUCACGAGGCGCAAUAGAUGUAACUGAAAGCUUCGAGAAGUUUAAAGGACUUGCAAGGAAAUCUACUGAAAUAAGCCCCAUUCCACCUGGGCAGAAGCACUCAGACGCCAAACCCCACCUUCUGUCCUGAAAUUCACCUUCCACUAGGAGAGUUUGCUUUUCUAAUGCUUCAAAUGCACAACGGGAGAUGUUCUGACUUCAGGGUUUCUACCCUUCACUGCUGUAAUCUGCUGCCUGUAUGACAUGCGAUCUGGUUUACACCGUACAGCUUAUCAUCUUCAGCUUGUGGCCCCUUCCUUGUUUCCACCUUGCUAUUCAGGAGGGCCUGUAAGGGUAUCUGGAUUCCUUGAGCUGUAGAUGCAGGACAGUGAGAGGGAGGGAGGUAGUUCUCUGGUCUAAUUUCAGUUUCCUAACUGAGGGUACAUGCCUUCCCUGAAUGAUCAUCAUCAAAAAUAUCCAGCCCUUCAUGGAAGACACCACCCCUCCUCAUAGAUGAGUCCCUGAGCUUAUGAUCUCAAAAGGAAAUCCUUAUCAGAAUACAACAGAAUAAGGACAUAGUUUCAUUACAGUUAUAAUAAUAAAAGUAGUUCUUCUUUAUUAA